AGCUGCGCACGAGGCCAGCGGCGGGGUCGCUGCCGUUGAGGCUUCCCGCCACUGCUGCUGGCGGAUUUGUGGGGCAAAAUUUCUCGCUGGCUAGCCUUCUUUUCCCUCCCGCACUUUGGUGGGGAGGGGGUGGAUCCUCGUUUCGGUGCCCAAGUUCACGAUGACCCGAGAGAACUCGAGGAAGUUGUCGCCGCGGCCAUUUCCCCCAGUGCCGCAACUUGCUGGCCUUGGAGGGGGAGGAGCGCCGAGGCAGUGACUGCGACGGUUAGCCCGCCCGUUCCUGCUGUCUUCGUUUGCAAAAUAGAUGCUAGAUCUCGAGGUUGAUUCUCAAGGGGAGGGGCCAGUGAGGGCACAUUGCUUUGGAGGAGUAGUUUAAUAAACUCUCUAGUGCUGGAAGUUUUAGCAAACGGAGGAGCCUUCAAACCCGGCAACAGUCCCCAUCUAGGUGUUUCCGUAACACAUGCGGAAUUAUUGCUAGUGGAAUUUCAGGCUUUCUUUGUUGUUUAACUCAAUGCAUCGCUAAUUGUUUAUAAUGAACUUAGAUGUUGCCUCCACCUGAGCCUUGCUAUUGCUAACAUUAAAAUAUUUUGUAGGCCUGGCGCGAUGGCUCCCGCCUGUAAUCCCAGCACUUUGGGAGGCCAAGGUGGGCGGAUCACGAGGUCAGGAGAUCGAGACCAUCCUGGCCAAAAUGCAAACAUCAAACCAGAUGCAAACAGAUUCAUUAUCUCCAUCCCCUAAUCCUGUGUCACCUGUGCCUUUGAAUAACCCAACAAGUGCCCCAAGAUAUGGAACAGUGAUCCCUAAUCGCAUCUUUGUAGGAGGAAUUGAUUUUAAGACAAACGAAAGUGAUUUAAGAAAAUUUUUUUCCCAGUAUGGGUCUGUGAAAGAAGUGAAGAUUGUAAAUGACAGAGCUGGAGUAUCCAAAGGGUAUGGUUUCGUCACUUUUGAAACACAAGAAGAUGCACAAAAAAUUUUACAAGAGGCUGAAAAACUUAAUUAUAAGGAUAAGAAGCUGAACAUUGGUCCAGCAAUAAGAAAACAACAAGUAGGGAUCCCUCGUUCUAGUAUAAUGCCAGCAGCUGGAACAAUGUAUCUAACAACUUCAACUGGAUAUCCUUAUACUUACCAUAAUGGUGUUGCUUAUUUUCAUACUCCAGAGGUAACUUCGGUCCCACCGCCUUGGCCUUCACGUUCUGUAUGUAGCUCCCCUGUGAUGGUAGCUCAGCCCAUUUAUCAGCAACCUGCAUAUCACUACCAGGGAAUUAAACAAUGUCAUACAAGAAGAUGGAUGGACUCUUUGCUUCCUUUUACCAAAUGUGAUGAGGCCACCACACAGUAUUUACCAGGACAGUGGCAGUGGAGUGUUCCUCAGCCUUCUGCCUCUUCUGCUCCAUUCUUAUACCUGCAACCUUCUGAGGUUAUUUAUCAACCAGUGGAAAUUGCACAGGAUGGUGGAUGUGUUCCUCCUCCACUGUCUCUGAUGGAAACUUCAGUUCCAGAGCCUUAUUCUGAUCAUGGAGUUCAAGCAACAUAUCACCAGGUUUAUGCUCCAAGUGCCAUCACUAUGCCUGCGCCUGUGAUGCAGCCUGAGCCAAUUAAAUGUGGAGCAUUCAUUAUUAAGACAAUUGGGCAGCUCUAUUCCAGCUCAACUGAUUUCUUGUCCAAUGAUCCUUGCGUGGCCGAGAUCCAGCUUCAACGAACCAGCUAGAAGCUGCCCGUUGUGAAACUUAGUGUUAGUUAAUACCUCACCAUACUCAGUUAUUCCACUAUAAGCUGUCUAAAUUUGAUGAAAUUUGCUUUUUCAGCUGUUCUACAAAAUUAUUUAGGUAGAUGUGGCAUGUUGGUUUUUUAUGUGCUAACCUAACUGUAAUGACCUUUUCUACAACAUGUUUUAUCCAUUCCAUAAAUAAUAACCACAUUGGGAAUAGUGAGGUGUCUUUUAUUUUCUCUGCUUUGUGUUAUUUUUUCUUAUCAAACAAUUAGAUGUUAUGUUUCAUAUUAUUUGAUAUUUAUUUUCAUAUUUAGGAUAAGAAUCAUUUUUAAUUAUAAUACUUUUAAUACUUUCAUAUAUUUUACAACAGUAUACUAUUUAAUAUUAAUGACAAUUCUAUUUUUGCUUUGCUGUUUUGUCAUUUAAUAUGCUUUUGUCUAAUUUUUAAUUCAUUUAUUACUGUUACUCCUUAUUUAAUUUUGCGUCUGCCAUGGUUUUCAGAAUCUGAAUAGUAUUUAUACUUCUUUUUUAUAACAUUUUCCAAAUAUUAGAAAUACCAUCAACAUGAUCAGUAUUCUUGCCUUUUCAUGUAAUUUGACUAUAUUAAAUUUUUUCUCCAGUGUUUGAGACAAUAUUGAAAUCUUCCUAUAACAUAAUUUAUUUGGUAUCAAAUUUUAUAAAAUAUGGAUCCACCUUUGGAAUUUUGAUAAAAGGGUUCAUCUCUGACAUGAUCCCAUAACACUGACUGAAAUUCCACCAAAUUACUGUUCUUUGAAUGCUUUAAUCCUUAAACCUUUUCUUCUGAUAUGCAACCAAUAUAUUCAAUUAUAUAUGUGAUUAAUUUUUAAAAGGACAAUUGUUUUCAUAAAAUGCAAAACUAUUUUUUACACCAAAGGAAAAUUUUAGAUUCUGAUUCUAAAUCCGAUUUUUACUAUAAAAUUGGAAAAUAGAUGGGAGGGGUGUCAUUCAUUGUUCAAAAGGUACAGAACAAAUCAUAGGGGUUUUUAAUCUCUAAAAUUUCUACAGUAGUACAGGAAAUAUUCCUCUUUACAUUCAUUUGCAGUUCUUUCACUGACCUCCUAAUUUUAGGUGGAGGGGGCAGGGGGAGCCAUAAAAGUUGGUAUUACCCUAAUAAAUCUAUCUCUUUCCUCCCCUGUUUCAACCCCACAUGUAUUCCAUGCUCAGCAGCAGCAGCAGAAAUAGUAGGAUAUAGAUCACAAAGGUUUUUCUGGUGAGUCAAAUAGGGUGUUUUCUUUUGAAACUGUAAUGAAUAUGUUUGCCAGUCAAAUGGCUUCAUGAGAACAGUAGAACCUUAUGAAUGUAUACUAGCAUACAAGGAUCUCAAAUACAUUAAUUAUUCUCAGUUUUAGGAAUGUAAAUAGAUUAAGUCCCACAAUGAAAUUUCAGAAGUUUUUGUUCUGUAAGUAAAAAAUUACUAACCACUGAUGUUCAAGAUUUUCUUUUAAUAGCACUAUCCUUGAGAACCAAAAAGUUUAUGUUUUGAUUUUCAAAUGUUAAACAAGAUGCUAAACAAAUCCUGGACUGUUAAUAAAAAUUAAUUAUGUAUUAUUGGA